AGCCCAGAUUAAGGUUGCAACUGGGUAGACCAGGAAGUGGGGAAACCGGUUUGUCAUUUGGGCCACUUGGGGUGGGGUCUCCUCUCCUGGGCUCUCUGCCUGCCUGCCACUCUGCCUGAUGGCCCACAGUGAAUAGAAGUACUGUGUCCACUCUCUUGCUCACCUAAACUGCUUUUGGAAACUCCAGAAGUAAAUAAAAGGGACAGGGGACUCAGCCCACCUUCUCCUCCGCAAGAAAGCUUGAGAGAGAAGGGACUGGCCAGAGCAUCGGAGCGAGGGAGGGAGGGGGCCGCUGGAAUCACGAGGUGUCGGCGCGGGCCUGGGUCUGGGUCUGGGUCCGGGUCAGCGCUGGAGAAGUCUGCGGAGCCAACAGAUCCGGAGCGGAGCAGCCCCCCCAUGCUGUCUGCGGACGAUGCGGAGUACCCGCGGGAGUACCGGACCCUGGGGGGCGGGGGCGGCGGGGGCAGCGGGGGCCGGCGCUUCUCCAACGUGGGGCUGGUGCACACGUCCGAGCGGCGGCACACGGUGAUCGCGGCCCAGAGUCUGGAGGCGCUCAGCGGGCUCCAGAAGGCGGACGCCGACCGCAAGCGUGAUGCCUUCAUGGACCACCUGAAGAGCAAGUACCCACAGCACGCCCUGGCCCUGCGAGGCCAGCAGGACAGGAUGCGAGAGCAGGUUGGCGGCUGGACCGUGGACCCCGUAUGCCUCCUCAGCUCCCUCUGCUCCCACCUCCAUGGCGACUCCGCCCCCUCCGGGGCUGGCCAGCCGGCCCAGCAGCCAAACUACUGGAGUUUCAAGACCCGCAGCUCACGCCACACUCAGGGAGCCCAGCCCGGGCUGGCAGACCAGGCGGCAAAGCUGUCCUACGCCUCCGCCGAGUCGCUGGAGACCAUGUCGGAGGCCGAGCUGCCCCUGGGCUUCAGCAGGAUGAACCGCUUCCGACAGAGCCUGCCUCUCUCCCGCUCGGCCAGCCAGACCAAGCUGCGCUCCCCAGGGGUGCUGUUCCUGCAGUUCGGGGAGGAGACUCGGCGCGUGCACAUCACGCACGAGGUCAGCAGCCUGGACACGCUGCACGCACUCAUCGCGCACAUGUUCCCGCAGAAGCUCACCAUGGGCAUGCUUAAGUCGCCCAAUACCGCCAUCCUCAUCAAAGACGAGGCUCGCAACGUCUUCUACGAGCUGGAGGACGUCCGGGACAUCCAGGACCGCAGUAUUAUCAAGAUCUACAGAAAGGAGCCCCUCUACGCUGCCUUCCCUGGCUCACAUCUCACCAACGGGGACCUCCGGAGAGAGAUGGUGUACGCAUCGCGGGAGUCCUCGCCCACGCGGCGCCUCAACAACCUGUCACCAGCGCCGCACCUGGCAUCCGGCUCGCCGCCGCCCGGGCUGCCGUCGGGGCUGCCGUCCGGGCUGCAGUCCGGUUCGCCGUCGCGUUCGCGCCUAUCGUACGCCGGGGGGCGCCCGCCUUCGUACGCCGGCAGCCCGGUGCACCACGCGGCCGAGAGGCUGGGAGGCGCCCCGGCCGCCCAGGGCGUCAGCCCCAGCCCCAGCGCCAUCCUGGAGCGGCGCGACGUGAAGCCGGACGAGGACCUGGCGAGCAAGGCGGGCGGCAUGGUGCUGGUGAAAGGCGAGGGCCUCUAUGCUGACCCCUACGGGCUGCUGCACGAGGGCCGUCUGAGCCUGGCCGCGGCCGCCGGCGACCCGUUCGCCUACCCGGGCGCCGGCGGCCUCUACAAGCGCGGCUCGGUGCGCUCGCUCAGCACCUACUCGGCCGCCGCGCUGCAGUCCGAUCUGGAGGACUCCCUGUACAAGGCGGCGGGCGGCGGCGGCCCGCUGUACGGCGACGGCUACGGCUUCCGCCUGCCGCCUUCGUCACCGCAGAAGCUGGCCGACGUGGCAGCACCCCCCGGAGGUCCCCCGCCACCGCACAGCCCCUACUCGGGGCCGCCCAGCCGCGGCUCGCCAGUGCGCCAGUCCUUCCGCAAGGACUCGGGCUCCUCGUCCGUCUUUGCCGAGAGUCCUGGAGGGAAGACCCGCAGCGCGGGGAGCGCCUCGACGGCCGGAGCUCCCCCUUCGGAGCUCUUCCCUGGGCCUGGGGAACGCUCGCUGGUUGGGUUCGGGCCGCCAGUGCCAGCCAAGGACACGGAGACCAGGAGAGACCCUAUGCUCAGAGGCGAGGUUGCCCAGACCCCCUUCCUCCCCAGGGAGCGCAUGGAGGCCAUGGAGAAGCAGAUUGCCAGCCUCACAGGCCUGGUGCAGAGCGCCUUACUGCGAGGCUCUGAGCCUGAGACCCCCAGCGAGAAGAUUGAAGGCUCCAAUGGAGCAGCCACCCCCUCAGCACCCUGUGGGUCAGGCGGCCGGAGCAGCGGGGCCACCCCGGUGUCCGGCCCGCCCCCGCCCUCGGCCAGCAGCACCCCCGCAGGUCAGCCUACCGCCGUUAGCCGGCUGCAGAUGCAGCUUCACCUGCGAGGCCUGCAGAACAGCGCCAGUGACUUGCGCGGCCAGCUCCAGCAGUUGCGCAAGCUCCAGCUACAGAACCAGGAGUCGGUGCGCGCGCUGCUGAAGCGCACGGAGGCAGAGCUGAGCAUGCGCGUGUCGGAGGCGGCGCGGCGGCAGGAGGACCCGCUGCAGCGGCAGCGCACCCUGGUGGAAGAGGAACGGCUGCGCUAUCUCAACGACGAGGAGCUUAUUACCCAGCAGCUCAAUGACCUGGAGAAAUCGGUGGAGAAGAUCCAGAGAGACGUGUCCCACAACCACCGGCUGGUGCCCGGCCCUGAGCUGGAGGAGAAGGCACUGGUGCUGAAGCAGCUCGGGGAGACGCUGACAGAGCUCAAGGCUCACUUCCCGGGCCUGCAGAGCAAGAUGCGGGUGGUGCUGCGCGUGGAGGUGGAGGCGGUGAAGUUCCUGAAGGAGGAGCCCCAGCGCCUGGAUGGGCUCCUCAAGCGCUGCCGCGGGGUCACGGACACGCUGGCCCAGAUCCGAAGGCAAGUGGAUGAGGGUGUGUGGCCACCCCCCAACAAUCUCCUGAGUCAGUCCCCCAAGAAGGUGACGGCAGAGACUGACUUCAACAAGAGCGUGGACUUCGAAAUGCCACCCCCCAGCCCCCCGCUGAACCUGCAUGAGCUGAGCGGGCCAGCUGAAGGAGCCUCUCUUACCCCCAAGGGGGGCAACCCCACCAAAGGCCUGGACACUCCUGGCAAGAGAAGCGUGGACAAAGCUGUGUCUGUUGAGGCUGCAGAGCGAGACUGGGAGGAGAAGCGGGCAGCCCUGACCCAGUACAGUGCCAAGGACAUCAACCGGCUGCUGGAAGAGACACAGGCAGAGCUGCUCAAGGCCAUCCCUGACCUGGACUGUGCCAGCAAGGCCCAUCCAGGCCCGGCCCCCACUCCAGAUCACAAGCCCCCCAAGGCCCCCCACGGCCAGAAGGCAGCCCCCCGAACGGAGCCCAGUGGGAGGAGGGGCUCAGAUGAGUUGACCGUGCCCCGAUACCGCACAGAGAAGCCCUCCAAGUCGCCCCCACCGCCCCCUCCCCGCCGGAGCUUCCCCUCCUCCCAUGGCCUGACCACCACACGUACCGGAGAGGUGGUGGUCACCAGCAAGAAGGACUCGGCCUUCAUCAAGAAGGCUGAGUCCGAGGAGCUGGAGGUGCAGAAGCCCCAGGUGAAGCUGCGCCGGGCUGUGUCUGAGGUGGCCCGCCCAGCCUCCACACCACCCAUCAUGGCCUCGGCCAUCAAGGACGAGGAUGACGAGGAUCGCAUCAUCGCAGAGCUAGAGGUGUUUGAGAGAAGCUCAGUGUCUUCCCUCCCCCCCACGCCCCGCCGCCAGCUGAUCCCCACCUUGCUGUCCCCCCAGGACCUGGGGCCCCCCGGGGGCUCAGCCCCAGGCCCUACACGGAAGCAUCGGGCAACGGAGCCGGGCGAGCGUGAGGUUGCCCUCUCUGCCUUCCCAGUCAGCACCCCCCACUUCCAGGCUGCCCCAGGUCCCAGGGCCUUCUGCGUCCCAAGGAUCAUCUUGACAGAGUGUGCCCCCAACCCUCCCUCCCCGCCAGAGGCCAGACUUGAGGAACUGGGACCCAGGACAGCUCCCACCCCAAGACCUCAGACCCUGGCUGACAGCACGAGGGGCUGGGAUGGCCCACAGUCCCCACCAGGGGUAGUGGGGGAGACUUCUGGGCCGAGGAGCAGCUUCAUGCCCCGGAAGGAGGGGGCAGCUCUGAAGAGACUGGGUGGAGGAGGCAGCAGCCUAGAGGAUGGAGGAGCCAGAGUACAGUGUCCUCAGGGACCAGCCCAGGAUGGGACUCCAGAGACCUCUACUGCUGACACCUACCCAGAGGAGAUCCUCAAGGACUCUGGACAUGAUGCCCAAACCUGCAGUAGGGAGCAUCAGGGCCAGGCUGCUGCCAACUCAGGCCGCACCACGUGGGGCGCCACUGCCCAGCAGAUGGACAGCUUGGAGGAGACGCUCCGGGAGCUGGAAGCCACCCUGAGCAACAUGGGCACAGGCCCUGCCAUGGGGUCCCCUGGCAGCCCCCCACCCCUACCCCUCCGCCCCCAGAGUGGCGGAGGCAGUGUACCACCCAUGAAGGUGGUGACUCCGGGGGCCUCUCGGCUGAAGGCGGCCCAGGGCCAGGCGGGCAGCCCCGACAAAAGCAAACAUGGCAAGCAGAGGGCCGAGUACAUGCGGAUCCAGGCCCAGCAGCAGGCCACUAAACCAUCUAAAGAGAUGAGCGGGUCGAAUGAGACCUCGAGCCCAGUCUCAGAAAAGCCCUCGGCUUCCAGAACCUCUAUCCCUGUAUUGACUUCCUUUGGGGCAAGGAAUUCUUCCAUCUCCUUCUAGAAGCCCCUCACCCCGCUGCCCCGCCUGUCCCCCUCCCUCACUCCUGCCAUUUCUCCCCUCUCUUCCUUCAUCUCCACCCCACCCCACCCUACUCUCCAGACGCCCUGAGGGGUGUGCCCUGAAGAGGAGGGUGCGGCCCUCCUCAGCGACCCCUACCCAUCAUCUGUUGGUGUUUUUGGUUUUGUUUUUUUUUUUUUUUUUAACAAUUAACUUUUAAUUAUCUUUUUUUAAACAGUAAAACUAAAAACCAAACACACCACCUUCCUUGAUCCCAGCUGGCCUCUCGCUGGCCGCACCUGUCACAUCUCUCCUUCUUCUCUUUCACCACUCUUUCCCCCAGUCCAUCCUGAAGCUCCUGCACCCCCUUCCCGCCUUCCCCUCACUUCCCAAGAAUACUCCAAACAAACUCUGAACCACGGAGACUUGGAGCAGUGGGAGACCCCUCUCCCGUUUCUCGAUACCUUCCUGGAGGAACGCGGGGACAUCGGACCAACCCAUACAUCAAGCCAGAGAGCGGGGCUUAGGGAGACUGGCCUUGGAGAUGCCCCACUCCCUGUCUAAGCUCCGACAAGACUGUGACUUCCUCUGUGGCUGCUCUGCCUCCUCCCACUCACACCCAAGUGGGCCUGGAGUAGAGACGGACAGGCUGGAGACGAGGCCGGAGUUUGAGAGGCCUCAGGGUGGGUGUGAGGCCAUGGAGUCUGUAUCCCUGGGGAGGCGCUGGCCUCCUGGGCCUUGCCGUCCAGUGGGGAGUGGAGGGCAGAGGCCCUUUGGUCUGCUGGCUGUGGAGGGUGGGUUGCACGGACAGCCGGAUAUCGGGGACACUGCCUUGGGAGAGGGCGGCCCGGACGGGUAUUUGGUACUUUUAGUUUCCUGAUUUAGCACUUUAAAUGGCAUUAACUUAUUGAAUGGGGAUGGGGUGGGCAAGAGUGAGGGGCCUAGAAAACCAGGUUUUGUGGCUUGCAGUUGGGGGAAGGGUCUGGUUUGAGGGAAAUGGGAGGGUCGAGAGGGGCUUGACGGGGAGCACUGAAGACACCUGGGACCCGCAGGUGGGGUGACUUGAACUUCAGUCAUCCUCUUGGCAAUUUGAGGGUUUUCCCAGGAAAGGAUGAGACGUAGUUUUUCAAUGGGGCUCUGGUGACCCUGGUGAGAUGUCUGAAGGUCCCUGAGGCCUGACCAUCCAGCCAGCGCCCCUGGCCUGUGGACGCCCUGCCUGCCCUGCAGAGGCGGUUGGCAGUGCCGCCUGGCUUUUGGCCGGGUCCUGGGGAGGCAGAGAGAGGCCAAUUUUGGUUCUCACUCCUGGCCCCCCAGAGGGCACAGUGAGGAGCCGGUAGGGAGAGGAUAGGAGAAGAGGAGGAGGAGGAGCGGGGUCCCCGGCCGCAGGAUUCCCACUUGGAGCACAAAGUGAAGUAAGCACAGGGGAGGGGGACUAGAAUCAGUCCCCCAUAGCAAGCACAGAAAGGAGGAGCUGCGCAGAAGGCAGAGCCCCCCAGACCCUGGGGCCUGGCUGGGGAAGGUCCGCACCUGGGGAGAGCUGGGAGCUGUUGAAGGUUUGGGGGGAGGGGAAACGGGUUGUGUUUCUUCAUUUCUUUUUUUGUUUUUGCCUUUGUUGGUUCAUCCUUGUUUUCUAGCUUUGGAUCAUUUUUGUACCAAGGCGAGCAAGCCUUUUUGAAAAAUAACAAAAGAGGAAAAAAAAAAUCCCUCCUGGAAAAAAAAAAAAACCCUGGAAAAUAGAAAAAAAAAAAAGGACCUCAUAAAUGAUGCAAUUACUUUUAAUUGCAGGCAACUCUUUACAUUUAAGUGAAGUGUCUUAACAUUUUAUAUUGUUUUAAAAAUAUAUUUACAUAUUAUAUAUAUAAUAUACGUAAUAUAAAUAUAUAUAAAUAUUUAAAAAAGAAAAAAAAAAGAAAACCACGGCACUCUCCCUGGCCACUGUUUUGGCGGGGGAGGGGGGCUGGGGGGCGGGCACGUCGGCCUGGCUUCUGUGGUCCCAGUGAAAUGGUCUGGUUUGAUUUGGCUGUACAGAGACCCCCUGACUUGGGAGGGGAGGGGGGAGUGGUGCCCCCUCCUCCCUCCACUCCAUUACUCUCUGCUUGCUACUUCGCUUGCCCCCAGCUCCCACCCUCAGCCCUGUGACUGGAAUGUGUGCCCCACCGUCAUUGUCCUGAGUUGAAUGUCCCUUUGUGGGGGAGGUGGGGGGGGCAGUGUCCAUCCACGAAGGGGCAGAAGGAGGGAGCCACGUGCCCCGCCCCACCCGCUCGGGUGAAGCCCAGUGGGAUUUGCAUCUUUCUUUCUCUUUGGUUCCUGCACAUUUAUGGGCUGGGAGGCAUCCGUGUGGAAUUGCGUGCAGCCUGUGUGUGUGCUGGCACAAGCCCAUGCACUGUGUGUGCAGACGCAUGGGGCCUGCACCCACAGGCAUGGCCGAGCACAUGUGUGGGGGAAGGCGUGGGCACAUAGGUGCAUGUAACCUGUUUGGGCAUUGGCACGUGCCUACCUGCAUGUUAGCGUGAGAGGAGCUUUGUGUGUGAGAACAUGUGUAAUGUGUGUGCAGACAUGCCGAGAGCCAGAGACUUGUGUGUGGGCCACGUACAUGUGGAUAGAGACGCAUACAUGGAGGUGCAUGUAAUCUGUGUCUCCGAGUGUGUGUGUGCAGGUAUGUGUGCUGGUGCAGACCCAAGUGUGUGGGUGUGCCUCUGUGUGCGUGUGUUCCAUCAUCCCUGCACCACUGGCUCCAGAUCCCUUCCUGAGCCCCCGUCCCCGCUGGCCCUCUCACAGCCUGCAGCACAUCAGUGCCCCCAGCUGCAUGCGCCUCGCUGCUCUGUCCAUCAGUGUGUGCUUGACCAAGAGAAAACUAAGACGUCUCGGGGGACCCCUGUACCUGGUCCUCUCAGCCCCCGCCCACUGUGCUGUGUUACUCGCAUGGGGGAUUUCCUGCCCCUUCCACAAUAUGCUGUUUCCCCAGGAGCCUCAGGCCUGAGGCUCUGAGUGGGGUCCCCAGGGGGCCCCCCGGGGUGAGCCCCGGCUCCACACCCUGCCCCAUCCACCCUGUAGGGCCCAUGUUGGUGUAGCAGUGAUGGCUUCUGUGGAUAUUCUGUGACCUCUGUCGGUGUAACUUGACAAUUUCUAAAUGGAAAAGGGUUGCUGUGUUUUCUCUGUCUCUCUUUUUUAAUGUCCUUUUUUCUUCUCCCCCGCUCCCUGCUCUCUUUCCUUUUCAGUUUUUCUAGCCAAGUGUUUGGGGCUUUAAUAAAACUUGUUUCUUUUUCCUCUCCUGGA